AAGCUGCCCGCAAUACGUCAUGGCGACCAAACGCCUUUUCGGGGCUACCCGGACGUGGGCCGGCUGGGGGGCCUGGGAGCUCCUAAACCCCGCCACUUCCGGAAGACUCCUGGCCCGGGAUUAUGCCAAGAAACCAGUUAUGAAGGGGGCCAAAUCGGGAAAAGGUGCAGUGACCAGCGAGGCCCUCAAGGACCCCGACGUAUGCACAGAUCCUGUCCAGCUCACCACAUAUGCCAUGGGCGUCAACAUCUACAAGGAAGGGCAGGAUGUACCCCUGAAACCGGAUGCUGAGUACCCUGAAUGGCUGUUCGAGAUGAACUUGGGUCCCCCAAAGACCCUGGAGGAGCUGGACCCCGAGAGCCGGGAGUACUGGCGGCGGCUGCGGAAACAGAACAUCUGGCGCCACAACCGGCUGAGCAAGAACAAGAGGUUGUAGCAUGGAGGGCCCGGCAUCGCUGACCCCCACGCCGAGGGCUUGCCGUUUUCCCGGAGGACGUGGACUUUUGUGAGACAAGAGGCGGCUCCCCAGCCUGGGUUUCCAUGUGACCCCACAGUGGGGCUGGACCAGGGCCCUGGAGGCCAAUAAAGAGCUUUCUGGGUAGACCCUA